AGGGCGCAGCGCGGCGCGGCCGGCGGGCGGGCGGCGCGGCGGCGGCGGCAUGGGCGCGGGCACCGGCGGGGGCUGCGGGCGCCCGGCUCCCCGCCCGGCCCGGCCCGCUCCCGGCGCGCGGCCGCCGCAGCCCUGGCAGCCGGCUGGGAGGCCGUCCCUGCACCCGGCGCAACUUGCCUCGGACCCUCUGUGAGGAGAGGCGGCGGCGGCGCGCGCCGGGCCGGGCGGGAGCGGGCGAGGCGUGCGGGCGCCCGGCGCGAUGCCUCCGGCCGGCGGCCCCCGAGCGCCGCGUCCCGCCGCGCUGCCCCGCAGCCUGUCCCGCCUGCGCGAGUGCCCGGGCCGCUCCCGCAUCGUGCUGGCGCUCGGGGCCACGCAGAUGGCGCUCGGAUGCCUCAUCGUGGCAGUCAGCUUCGCCGCGCUGGCGCUCACCACCUCGGCCCGCGUCCGCCACUCCUGCCCCUUCUGGGCAGGCUUCUCGGUGCUGCUGUCGGGACUCAUAGGUGUCGUCUCCUGGAAGAGGCCUCUCUCCCUUGUGAUAACCUUUUUCAUGCUGCUUUCUGCGGUGUGUGUAAUGCUGAAUUUGGCUGGUUCAAUUCUCUCUUGUCAGAAUGCUCAGCUAGUCAACUCCCUAGAAGGCUGCCAGUUGAUUAAGUUUGACAGUGUGGAGGUGUGUGUCUGCUGUGAGCUGCAGCACCAGUCGUCCGGCUGCAGCAACCUCGGGGAGACGCUGAAGCUGAACCCGCUGCAGGAGAACUGCAACGCUGUGAGGCUGACCUUGAAGUCCUCCAUGGGUGGUCUCCGGCUGGUAGACAAGCAAAGAUGUACAGAGAGAGAGGAUGCGGCUCAUCUCCAUGGUAGGACUACGCCUGGCUCACAGCGCCUGUCAUGUUUUGCACGGAGGAAUGGUCCAAGUUGGAUGGUCCCAGCAGCUCACCAGAGUGACAGAUGCAGCGGGGUUGGAGGAAUCAAGAACUGCAGCACUCCAGGGCCCAUCCCAUCAUGGGACCAGGAUCUCCUCUUCAGCGUGUGUGCCCUCAACGUCCUGUCCACUAUCGUGUGUGCGCUGGCCACAGCCAUGUGCUGUAUGCAGAUGGUCUCCUCCGAUGUCCUGCAGAUGUUCCUUCCGCAGAGGUCACAUCCUGCCAACCCCACCUGCGUGACUCCUCACGGCACCGUUCUCCACCAGACCCUGGAUUUCGACGAGUUCAUCCCCCCACUCCCGCCUCCACCCUAUUACCCCCCAGAGUACACCUGCACACCGUCCACUGAGGCCCAGAGGGGCCUCCACCUGGACUUUGCUCCGUCUCCAUUCGGCACUUUGUAUGACGUGGCCAUCAAUAGCCCCGGCCUGCUCUAUCCUGCUGAGCUCCCCCCUCCGUACGAGGCGGUGGUGGGCCAGCCCCCUGCCAGCCAGGUUACAAGUAUAGGUCAGCAGGUGGCCGAGUCCAGCUCCGGGGACCCAAACACCAGUGCUGGCUUCAGCACUCCAGUACCAGCUGACAGCACAAGCCUCCUGGUGUCCGAGGGCACUGCUACGCCAGGUUCCAGCCCAUCCCCCGAUGGCCCUGUGGGCGCCCCAGCACCCUCCGAACCUGCCCUUCCCCCUGGCCGCGUGUCUCCAGAGGAUCCUGGCAUGGGCUCACAGGUGCAGCCAGGUCCCGGGCAUGUGUCCCGCUCCACCAGCGACCCCACCUUGUGCACAUCUAGCAUGGCAGGCGAUGCCUCUUCACACAGGCCGUCGUGUAGCCAGGACCUGGAAGCGGGACUGUCUGAGGCUGUGCCUGGGAGCGGCUUUCCAGUUGCCACCAAACAAGACACCAGAACAGACGACCCAGAAUGUUCCAACUUUGUGUGGCGUGAAGCUCAGGCUGGGCAAGCCGGGCCUUCGCUGGUCCUUGUUGGCGUCCCUCGCCACUGACAGCCCGGAGCUGGCCGUCUUACAGGGACCCUCAGCCCAGUGUCCAGCCUGUGGGUCAUGCAGAGAGGCUGUCAGCUCUGUGGGGAGCUGGAGCCAGGUCCCCAGCCUCUGGCCUGGCAGGCAGUGGAGCAGGGCACUGAGUGGUGGCUGCCUGCACCUGGCAUGAUGGGGGGGGCGGUCUCAUGUUCCCUCUGCCACCCCCAGUUCUGGUCUUAAGGCAGACCCUGUCUCUAGAUGCCAUGAUUCUGCCCCAGCAAGAGAUCAGACCCAAAGGGGCAAAGGUCGUGGAGGCGAGAAGACUGGGAAGGACCAGCCCCUGUGCCCUUGGGAUUCUAGCAGAGGGCAGAAGUGGGUCGCUGCCUGCUGUGGUGGCCCUUCCCCCCAGGCCUUCGCUCCUGGAGGCUGCAGCCCCUGGAGGUUGACACUAGUUCAGUUUGGGGUUGAGAAGGGGAGGAGGGAUGGGGACAGCAGGGCAUGCCCAGAGCGCCAGCCCCAGGAACACAGAAACCCCAGCAGGAGGCUCCUCCCGAGCAGGCUUUUCUUUGCUUUUGAGUUAACUUCUUAUUUCAGUGAGUUUUGAACUGCACUUUUGCCCUUGAUUUUUAGCUUCCAUGUCUCGCUCUGCCACGGCUGCCUGUCGGGCCCAGCUUUCACCAGCGGGGGACCCAGAUACCUGGAAAACUGACCAACGGCCAACACCAGAGCCCUUCCCAGCGACCUCCAAAGAGCGGCCACGCUCUUUAGUGGACAGCAAGGCCUAUGCGGACGCCAGGGUUUUGGUGGCCAAGUUUUUGGAACACUCACACUGUGCCCUCCCCACCGAGGCACAGCACAUGGUGGGUGCCAUGCGCUUGGCUGUCACCAACGAGGAGCGCCUCGAGGAGGAGGCCGUCUUCGGCGCUGAUGUUCUGGACCAGGUAUGAAGGAGCCACAUUUCUGACCGUGGACACCAACGCCUGGCGCCACAGAUGUUCUUGGCAGAAGCCAUCAUGCCUGACAAAGAGGCCUUCAGGCCCAGCUUGGCGGAGGAUAAAUGUGGGGGGGACACCCAGGAUGAUCUGGGGGCGGUGUGGGCAGGGAACUGUUACCCCCUCUCUCGAGGGGAGCCGAGCAGUGUCUCUUUGGGGAUUGCAUUUCCUGCCUAGCCCAGUAAUUCGGAAAGAUGACUUUCACGUCCACAGUGAACUCUCUGGUUUUAUCUGGCGUGCAGCACCUUGAACUGAGCAGUGUUGCACAAAUGUGAAUACAGCAACAGGCGACACUUACGUCACCUAAAGACUCAAAGUAUCUCCAAAAUCAGGGCCUUCCAAAGCAGGAGUCUCCCAUCCCCCAUUUAACUUAGUGUUCAGUGGACAGAGGGUGACAUCGAGUCAUGAAACAUUUUCUCAUGUGGCUCGAUGGCUCUAUCAUUAGGCGUUCAUCACGCUCUGGCCUAUUUCCUGUGAAAGGAAAUAGGUAGUGUUAGCACAGAUGGCAGCCUGGGCCCAACUUUCUGUCCACAGGGCUAUUGUGCAAACAAAUGUGCAGUGCGGGCCUCUGCCAUAGCCCGGCCCCCCCCAGGGAACAGGCCGGUGUUGCGGGGGUUGGAGGAACCCACCAUCUCCUGGGCCUUGAGCUCGGCCUCCCUCCGUGGGGUGCCUUCCCCCCCUCCUCUUGGGCCCCCUUUCUCCAGGCUCCCAUCCUGUCCCUGGAGCAGUUGUGUGAUCCGUAACAACAAGUGCCGAUUCCCAGCUCCUUUGUGUCUGAGCUCACUUGAUUGAGCUCAGCGGGUCACAGUUCUGCAGGAGAGAGGCCGGUUUCUCUGAGAAGUAGCCCCUCCUGAUAAAGCAGGUCCCUUUGACCCAGAGCUGACCUUUCCCCGGGCAUGCGGCAGCAGACACACCUGCGCAGGAGGAUCAUAAACCACUUACAAACCCACGCGAGAAGGGAAGCAGACACCCAACGUGCUGCUUAUGGAGAAGCAGACACGCCCAGCUUGGGGACAGCCUGGGGACCUUGGACUUUCUUAGCCCCCAUCCCCUUGUUUUCUGGUGGCAUCAGUGGCAGCUGCUCCCAACAAUGGCCGUGGAACAGCGCCAUCCACGAGAACUUUGUGCAGUGAUGGAAAUGCCUGUUCAGGGCCACUAGCAGCCACAGCCCCUGAGCUGCGUUGGGUGGGCCCUGCGGUGAACAAAACAGCCUAGAGGCCAAGGUCUCCCCAGAGAGCCCAUGAGCCUGGCAUGGGGGCACAGGGGGACCAGAGGGUGUCUUCCACUCCUGGGUGCCAGGGCAGGGGGCUCACGCUGCUGUUCCCUCGGCUUUGUGGGGCUUGUCCUUGAGCUCCCCCAAUUCCCUAAUGCCACUGUGGCCAGUGUGCUGGGGAGCUUCUGUGUGGCUGGAAGCUGGGAAGGGGGUGAGGUUCCAAUCCAGGUGCCCAGAGCCUUCCUCCAGUCCUUUAUCCCUGCCCUGGGGGCUGCGGUGUGGGACUCCUUCAGCUGUGGUCGGCUGAAAAGGCUUCGAUUGCUUUAGAGAGCUGAAAACACAUAAGCCAGGCCUUUUGAUGACAACCUGCACUUUUGCAGGAGAGACGUACUAGAGAUGAAUUUUUGAGCACUUUAUUCAGACUAUAAAACAGGAAAUCUCUAAUUUUCCUCAAGUGGGGGCUUUUGAAUUCCCUCAAGGCAAGUCCCUUUGCAGGUGAAAUUAAUUGGUGGAUUUUCAGAAUGGCCGCCCUGGAGCCGAGCUUCAGCCACGCCUGACGCCCUGGCCUCUGAAUCUCCACUGUCUCUGAGGUGCGCUGGGGCCACACCGCAGGGGUUUCACCUGCUUGGGGGGGUCCACACUAGGGCUUGGGGGUUCACACAGCAUUGUCCCUGGGCUGAGCCCUUGGGUGGGCUAGAGCUGCAGUCCUCAGACAUGGCUGCAAUUCCAGCGAGGCCAAGACCACCAGCCACCCAGUGGACUCGGUCUCUGGGGUGUUCUCCUCAUGCAGCCGGGGCAGAGGCCUACUGGACCCCCUCAGCCUGCUGCUCAGCAUCCUUCCCUUCUCUGCAGCAGGGCCCGGUCCCAAUGGCCAAUGGGGCUGCUGCCCCAGCAGUGCCUCCCUGCGGGCCCCUCACCUGCACCCCACCUUCACCCAGCUCUGGGUUUGCGCUGGUGGCAGCUCUGUUUUGUGGAUACGGAAACUGUACCCAACUUGAUGCCGCUGGGCUGGAACCUUCUGCCCCUUCGAAAUGAGGCAGUCAGGGACGGGGUGGGGUGCCCCCAUCAGCCCCGCUGCUCAGGGCCACUCAUGGACUCUAGGAGGGUCCAGGUUCUGGGCUUCCUGGGAAGGUCCCCAGAAGAGAGAGGUGCUGGUAGACUAGGGAAUGUGCUGGCAACUUGACCCAGCAGCUGUGGUCCCCUUGGCCCCGGCUCCACGGUAUCCGGGUACCAGCAGCAAGAGCCCAGGCCCCGGGCUGCACGUCAGCUCACAGCCCAGGAGAAAGCUGGCUGCUUCCCCUCCCUAUGCGUCUUUCCCCCGCUCCAAUCAUGCUCCCUCUGGGAUCUGAAAUGGGCCAACUGUGGCUGCUUUGGGGGUGACACGCUCCUUCUCCAACUCAGCUGGGCCCCGGGCAUCCCCUGCCCUCCCCUGAGACCCAAAGGGGGUUGGCACCUGCUGUGACACCACCGUUGACCCCAGCCUGGGGGCCACAAGGUUGCUGAGUGGGGAGAACAUGGACCCCAACUCUAUGGCAAGCAAGAUCGCAGAAGGGGGAGCAUCAUCCGCAAGGACUUCAGGUCUCCCUUGGCUGGAGAUGAGGAUCCACAUUAAAUGUUUGUAACACACCAGGCCACAGAAAGCUCGCUACACACAGAUGCUUCUCCCCACCCAUGCUGACUCUCAGAGGCUGCUAAGGCAGAAUUUAUAGGAAAUUGUUUUCAAGCCACCAGAGACCUGUCUGUACAACUGGAAAGGCUGUAUUUAUUUAAUGUACCUCAAGGUGUUUUAAUAAUGAUCCGUGUUUUAAUAAAAAGAAGUAUUUCUGGCC